AGAAACUUGCCCGUGCUCAAGAGAGGUGGGGAAAAAGAGUGAGAGGCGGCCAGAUGAACUCUACCGUCCGCCAGCUCCGCGUUCCUUCGCACGUGCCUCUGCGGGAUCCCUCGUGGGAAAGUCUCAGAAAUGUCCCUAAACUGAAGAAAAGCCGGGGAAUGCAAGGAGAGCAAGGUCGUAGGUUGUUCCGACUGCUCCUUAACGACCUGCCUGGCAGGGACCGACUACCCUGCUCCUACCCGCAGCCCCAUGUGGAGCAGGCAUCCACCAGUGCCUCCCCGCGCUUGCUAGCAGUGAACAUUCCUGAAGACACUCUCCUCUCUUAUCCUGAAUCCUCGCUCCCACUGCAGAGACACUGCGCCUUCCAUAGGUUCUCCAAGGCCAAAUUUGAGUCCCUCUUUAGGACGUAUGACAAGGACAUCACCUUUCAGUAUUUUAAGAGCUUCAAACGAGUCAGAAUAAACUUCAGCAACCCCUUCUCCGCAGCAGAUGCCAGGCUCCAGCUGCAUAAGACUGAGUUUCUGGGAAAGGAAAUGAAGUUAUAUUUUGCUCAGACCUUACACAUAGGAAGCUCACACCUGGCUCCGCCAAAUCCAGACAAGCAGUUUCUGAUCUCCCCUCCCGCCUCUCCGCCAGUGGGAUGGAAACAAGUGGAAGAUGCGACCCCAGUCAUAAACUAUGAUCUCUUAUAUGCCAUCUCCAAGCUGGGGCCAGGGGAAAAGUAUGAAUUGCACGCAGCGACUGACACCACUCCCAGCGUGGUGGUCCAUGUAUGUGAGAGUGAUCAAGAGAAGGAGGAAGAAGAGGAAAUGGAAAGAAUGAGGAGACCUAAGCCAAAAAUUAUCCAGACCAGGAGGCCGGAGUACACGCCGAUCCACCUCAGCUGAACUGGCACGCGACGAGGACGCAUUCCAAAUCAUACUCACGGGAGGAAUCUUUUACUGUGGAGGUGGCUGGUCACGACUUCUUCGGAGGUGGCAGCCGAGAUCGGGGUGGCAGAAAUCCCAGUUCAUGUUGCUCAGAAGAGAAUCAAGGCCGUGUCCCCUUGUUCUAAUGCUGCACACCAGUUACUGUUCAUGGCACCCGGGAAUGACUUGGGCCAAUCACUGAGUUUGUGGUGAUCGCACAAGGACAUUUGGGACUGUCUUGAGAAAACAGAUAAUGAUAGUGUUUUGUACUUGUUCUUUUCUGGUAGGUUCUGUCUGUGCCAAGGGCAGGUUGAUCAGUGAGCUCAGGAGAGAGCUUCCUGUUUCUAAGUGGCCUGCAGGGGCCACUCUCUACUGGUAGGAAGAGGUACCACAGGAAGCCGCCUAGUGCAGAGAGGUUGUGAAAACAGCAGCAAUGCAAUGUGGAAAUUGUAGCGUUUCCUUUCUUCCCUCAUGUUCUCAUGUUUGUGCAUGUAUAUUACUGAUUUACAAGACUAACCUUUGUUCGUAUAUAAAGUUACACCGUUGUUGUUUUACAUCUUUUGGGAAGCCAGGAAAGCGUUUGGAAAACGUAUCACCUUUCCCAGAUUCUCGGAUUCUCGACUCUUUGCAACAGCACUUGCUUGCGGAACUCUUCCUGGAAUGCAUUCACUCAGCAUCCCCAACCGUGCAACGUGUAACUUGUGCUUUUGCAAAAGAAGUUGAUCUGAAAUUCCUCUGUAGAAUUUAGCUUAUACAAUUCAGAGAAUAGCAGUUUCACUGCCAACUUUUAGUGGGUGAGAAAUUUUAGUUUAGGUGUUUGGGAUCGGACCUCAGUUUCUGUUGUUUCUUUUAUGUGGUGGUUUCUAUACAUGAAUCAUAGCCAAAAACUUUUUUGGAAACUGUUGGUUGAGAUAGUUGGUUCUUUUACCCCACGAAGACAUCAAGAUACACUUGUAAAUAAAGCUGAUAGCAUAUAUUCAUACCUGUUGUACACUUGGGUGAAAAGUAUGGCAGUGGGAGACUAAGAUGUAUUAACCUACCUGUGAAUCAUAUGUUGUAGGAAAAGCUGUUCCCAUGUCUAACAGGACUUGAAUUCAAAGCAUGUCAAGUGGAUAGUAGAUCUGUGGCGAUAUGAGAGGGAUGCAGUGCCUUUCCCCAUUCAUUCCUGAUGGAAUUGUUAUACUAGGUUAACAUUUGUAAUUUUUUUCUAGUUGUAAUGUGUAUGUCUGGUAAAUAGGUAUUAUAUUUUGGCCUUACAAUACCGUAACAAUGUUUGUCAUUUUGAAAUACUUAAUGCCAAGUAACAAUGCAUGCUUUGGAAAUUUGGAAGAUGGUUUUAUUCUUUGAGAAGCAAAUAUGUUUGCAUUAAAUGCUUUGAUUGUUCAUAUCAAGAAAUUGAUUGAACGUUCUCAAACCCUGUUUACGGUACUUGGUAAGAGGGAGCCGGUUUGGGAGAGACCAUUGCAUCGCUGUCCAAGUGUUUCUUGUUAAGUGCUUUUAAACUGGAGAGGCUAACCUCAAAAUAUUUUUUUUAACUGCAUUCUAUAAUAAAUGGGCACAGUAUGCUCCUUACAGAAAAGUUGUCAUUUUAUUUCUAGAAUAAAUCUGUGAACCUUCUAAA